AAGGCUCCUCAGCCGAGCGCCGAGCGGUCGAUCGCCGUAGCUCCCGCAGCCUGCGAUCUCCAGUCUGUGGCUCCUACCAGCCAUUGUAGGCCAAUAAUCCGUUAUGGAGCAUGCCUUUACCCCGUUGGAGCCCCUGCUUUCCACUGGGAAUUUGAAGUACUGCCUUGUAAUUCUUAAUCAGCCUUUGGACAACUAUUUUCGUCAUCUUUGGAACAAAGCUCUUUUAAGAGCCUGUGCCGAUGGAGGUGCCAACCGCUUAUAUGAUAUCACCGAAGGAGAGAGAGAAAGCUUUUUGCCUGAAUUCAUCAAUGGAGACUUUGAUUCUAUUAGGCCUGAAGUCAGAGAAUACUAUGCUACUAAGGUGUUAAUUUUCUCAAUAUUGGGCACAUCUUUCAAAGAAGAGAAGGAACCUUUCUCAGGAAGGAGGGAAGAGAAAAAGGGAUGUGAGCUCAUUUCAACUCCUGAUCAAGACCACACUGACUUUACUAAGUGCCUUAAAAUGCUCCAAAAGAAGAUAGAAGAAAAAGACUUAAAGGUUGAUGUGAUCGUGACACUGGGAGGCCUUGCUGGGCGUUUUGACCAGAUUAUGGCAUCUGUGAAUACCUUGUUCCAAGCGACUCACAUCACUCCUUUUCCAAUUAUAAUAAUCCAAGAGGAAUCGCUGAUCUACCUGCUCCAACCAGGAAAGCACAGGUUGCAUGUAGACACUGGAAUGGAGGGUGAUUGGUGUGGCCUUAUUCCUGUUGGACAGCCUUGUAUGCAGGUUACAACCACAGGCCUCAAGUGGAACCUCAUUCUCAUUAUUUCCAAGGGCACCCAAUCUAGACAGUGAUGAACUUCCUGCUGGAUCUAGGAGCGAUCACACUUUUCAGGGCUGGCAGCAAGACAAAGGAGCACUGAGCAAAGAGGACCGUUGGCACUAGGAGCAGGUGCCCCAGCUUCCUUUAUCUUAUAGUAAUAAAAAAGAGUCAUAUGUUAGACAUGAUUCUUCUGUUAUCUUUAGAAUGUCCUUUGAUCCUAUACUUCCCACAGUAGUAUGCACAUUGUAUUAGUCCAUGCUCACAUUGCUGUAAAGAACUACCUGAGACUGGGUAAUUUAUGAAGAAAAGAGGUUUAACUGACUCACAGUUAUGCAGGCUUACCAGGAAGCAUGACCAGGAGGCCUCAGGAAACUUACAGUCAUGGUGGGAGGUGAAAGGGAAGCAGGCACCUUCUUCACAUGGCAGCAAGAGAGAAUGAGAGCGAUGGGGGACGUGCCACAGACUUUUAAACCAUCAAAUCUCAUGAGAAGUCAGUCACUACCACGAGAACAGCAAGGGGGAAGCCCACUCCCAUGAUUCCGUCACCUCCCACCAGGUUCCUCCACCAACAAUUGGGAAUUACAUACAAUUCAACAUGCAAUUUGGGUGGGGACCUGGAGUCAAAUCGUAUCACACAUCCUAAUUCUGUGUAAGGCUUUCUCUGGUAAGGGGGCCUUCAGCAUGAUGAGGGCAGGGCUCUUAACCUUCCUGAGAUAACUUUUGAUCCGGCCUGCAUGUAAUAUGCCAUUACUUAUUUAUAUAGUUACACAUCACUUUGACUUUUGAAGUAAUUAUUUUUUCUAAACUUCAUAAAAAUAAAAAAAAAACUUCAUGGCAUAUGCAAAGCAAUAAAGUUGAAAUACAAAGUGUUUCAUCAAUUACCUGUUGUAAAAGCGCUAAUUCAUGGGGUCUUCUGAUAGGUAAUAUUGCCUCAUUAAAAGUUAAUAAAAAUAAAUGUGACAUCAUGUUGACUUGAAGAAAAGUGGGUAGAUUUCAUUCACAGAGAGGGUCCCUGCCUUCCUCAGUGCUGUUGUCUGUGAAAGAGCCCUGAGGUCAGGGUUAUUUUGUCAGUCAUGGCUACAAAGGGACAGGGUGAAGGUGGGCUUGCAGAAAGAGAAAGAAUAUGCAGACACUUAGUCAGGGGCAGCUCACUUCUUGGGUUAAUGGGAGUAAGCAAGUUUUUGUGAAGAAACUUGUCAAGGUCCUCAUGUGCGGCCCCGUGGCUUGAUCUCUACCUAUCUCCACCCACUCUAAGUACAUGAUGCCACAAGUUCUAAAAGUAGUUGGAUUUAUCUGUUACCAGUUCGCAAUAUUUCACAUGCCAUUCUAACGUUUAAAAAAAAAAAAUUGUGUGACUGAUACCUAGGUACCGAUCACCCAGGAGUGAAACGUUUCAAAUAUUACUGAAGCUGCCUAUGUUUACAGUCUUUUAUUUCAUAGCAAUAUGCUAUGAAUAUUCUUUGACUUGUGUCUUGUACAAGAGUUUCUCUAGGAUAUAUACAGUUGGCAGUAAAAUAGCUGUGUCAUAGAUAAUCACAUCUUCACCUUUGUGAGAUACACCAUAUUGCUCUACACAGUGAUUGUACCCAUGUGUAUUCAGCCCAGGAAUACAUAUUAAGUUCCCCUGCUCCAUAUCGUCAACAAUUCUUGCUAUUACCAAACUUAAUCAUUUUUGUCAGCCUGAUGAGUGUAAAUGAUAUGUUUUUGUGGUCUCUGCUGAUAAGGAUAAGCAUCUUUUUGUAGUUAUUAUUCAUGCUGGUUUCUUCUUCUGUGAAUUGCUACUUUCUUUUGCCUAUUUUUCCAUUGGGAUGUUAAUUCUUAGAAGUUCUGAAGCCUCUUUUUCCUGGCCGUACUUUGGCUUUUCAAUUUGUUUAUGGUGUUUUUAUAUGAACAGAGUUUAUUGAGUUAAAUGCAGUCAAAAUUUAUCAGUUUAGUCAUUUUCGUGUAAGUUAUCUUUCUAUUCCCCAUGGUCAUAAAGAUACUCUCAUUUAAGUUUCGUGUUUAGGUCUUUUCUUUCACCUGAAGUUGAUUUUUGUAUAUGAUGUAAGGAUCUAGUUUUUUAAAGAUAAUGAAUUGCCCUAACAUCAUUUAUUAAUCCUUUCUCCAGUGAUUUGCAGUGUAGCACAGGUGUUCAUAUGUAUGGGUAUGUUUCUUGGAUCUGUUUUGUUCCAUUGGCUUACAUACCUGUUCCUGUGCUGGAGCCACGCUGCCUUCAUUACCAUAGCUUUAUAAUAAAUAUUGAAAUGUGCUAAGUUGAGUCCUCAGACCUUGUUCUUCAAAAUUGUCACUCUAUUCCUGGCAUUUUGCUCAUUUGUUUGUUCGAGACGGAGUGUCUCACUGUCGCCUGGGCUGGAGUGCAAUGGUGCAAUUUCGGCUCACUGCAACCUCCGCCUCCUGGGUUCAAGUGAUUCUCCUGCCUCGGCCUCCUGAGUAACUGGGAUUACAGACGACUGCCACCACACCCAGCUAAUUUUUGUUUUGUUUUGUUUUGUUUGCAUUCUUAGUAGAGACAGGGUUUCACCAGGUUGGCCAGGCUUGUCUCCAACUCCUGACUUUGUGAUUCACCCACCUCGGCCUCCCAAAGUGCUGGGAUUACAGGCAUGAGUCACCACACCGGCCUGCUCUUCUUUAUAAAUUUUAGAAGUAACUUGACAAGUGCCUCUCUCACACAAUUCUAUUAUAAUUUUUGCUGCAAUUACAUUUAAUGUCUAGAUUAAUUUGGGAAGACUCAAAAAAUUGGGGAAGGAAAUUUCUACAUGAAAUUGAGUCUUCCCAUCCACAAAUUUAGUUUAGCUUUCUAUUUACUUAGAACUUUUAAAUUCCUUUCAAUAAUUUUAUAACUUUCUCUAUAAACAUCCUAUGCAUUUUUAUAAGGUUUAUUUCUAUAAACCCUAUAUUUUGUGUCCUAGUAUAAAUUAUACUUUAAAAAAUUACAUUUUCUGUUGGUGAUAUAUAGACAUAUAAUUCAUUUUUGUCUAUUUUAAUGUUAACAUAUUGAUGAACAUUAAUUAUAUCUGAAAACGUGACUGUACACUCACUUGGUUUUCUAUACACAAUCGUAUUUCUGUUAAUAAUCAAGUUUUCUUCUGCAGUCUGUAACAAAUAGAAUUAAGUUACUAUAAUGGACUGAAAUGGUGGCUUUAAAAAAAAAGCCUUUUUGUUGGUUUCCUCAUGUAGCAAAGUGCAGAGGUAAGUACCUACAGGGCAAGGUUUCUAUUAUUUCCUCAGCCUUUGCCUGAAAAUCUAAGAUGUCUUUUGCAACUCCAGCUGUAUUGUGCCCAGUAGGCAUCAGAAGAGAGGAAAGGGAAGGGAGCAGGAAGGAUCUGUAACGGGAAUCAGAGACAUCAGGGAUUCCCGGCAUUCUCAGAAACCCUUCCUGUGUCUCAUCUUUUGCCUCAGUGGCCAGAAUUGUAUCACAUAGCCACCCUAGCUUCAAGGAAGGCUACGUGUGCAAUUUUGAAUCCAACUACAUUGUCACUCCAAAUAAAACUGAGGUUCCAUCAGUAGGGAAGAAGAGAAUGACUAGGAGUCUGCUCUUCUGUCAAAAAAUGCCUUUGCUUCAUUCAUCAUCUUGAACAUUUUAUCUAUGUAUAUCUUAAAAAAUUUAUUUUAGUUUUCUUUCAGCCAUAUUCAUAUGGAUUGCUGUUGUUUCUGUUGAAAAAAUCUACAAUCAAUGAAAUUAGUUCUGAUUUGUUUAUAAUCUGUCACGUUUUCUAGACCUUAAGUUUUGCUUUGAUAUUCUAAAGUUUUACAACAAUAUGUUUGCAUGUAACGUUUCUUUUGUUCUAGUUGCUUUUUAUUCAUUCUGAUAAUUGGUAUAGUUCAUCAAUUCUGAAAAUUCUUAGCCGUUUAUCUUCUUCGAUUGCUUCCCCUCCAUUUUUUUCUAUUCUUUUCUCCUUGAACUGUUAGUAAACAUAUUAGGCCUCAUCAUCCCUUUUCCUUGUUUAUUCUUUGUGCAUUCUAUGUUUGUUUGUUUGUUUGUUUUCAUCUUUCUUUUCACUGUUUCUGUCUUUGGCUGUUUCUAAUCUGCCAUUUAAUGAUUGUGUUUUGAAUUUCAUAGAUUUUAUUUUUCACUCUUUUUUAUCUCAAAAAAUUUAAGAUCACGUCUUGUUUGUUGCCAGUAUUUUAAUUAUAUAUUUACUUUUUUAAAUAUGUAAGCAGAUUUUUAAAAUAUCAGAAAUUGAGAUGAAUUAUUUAAUCUAUUAGAUUGUUAAAAAUCAUAAUUUAAUUGAUAGGAGUUUUUUUAGAUAUUUAAAAAUUGGGGCCUAUUAUAAUACAUGGUAUCUUAUAUUUGGUGGAAUACAAUAUGGUAUUUGAGCAUUCUAGUUUCUUCAUCUCUUUUUUGACCUAAUUCUGCUAUUUUCCUUUUUUUUAUUUUUUGAGAAGGAGUCUCAAAUUUUCUGUUUCCAAUUACUUUUAAUGUUUCUUUUAGGUUCAGAGGUACAUGUGCAGGUUUGCUAUAUAGGUAUAUUGCAUGUCACAGGGGUUUUAUAUACAGAUUAUUUUAGCACCCAGGUAAUAAGCAUAGUAUCCAAUAGGUAAUUUUUCAGUCCUUACCCUGCACCCUCAACUAGACAUUGGCAUCUGUUGUUCCCUUCUUUGUGUCUAUGUGAACUCAACAUUUCACUUCCACUUAUAAGUGAGAACAUGUAGUAUUUGGUUUUCUGUUUUUGUGUUAGUUCACUUAGGAUAAUGGCCACCAGCUCCAUCUAUGUUGCUGCAAACGCAUGAUCUUGUUCUUUUUAUGGCUGUGUGAUAUUCCAUGGUGUAUAUGUACCACAUUUUAUUUAUCCAGUCUACCGUUGAUGAGGAUUUCAGUUGAUUCGGUGUCUUUGCUAUUGUGGCUAGUGCUGUGAUGGACAUACAUGUACAUGUUCUUUAUGGUAGAAUGAUUUCUAUUUCUUUGGAUAUAUACCCAAUAAUGGGAUUGCUGGGUCAAAUGGUAAUUCUGCUUUGAGUUCUUUGAAAAAUCGCUAAACUGCUCUCCACCAUGGCUGAACUAAUUUCCAUUCCCACCAGCAGUAUAUGUGUUCCUUUUCUCUUCAGCCUCACCAGCAUCUAUUAAUUUUUUGCCUUUUUGAUAAUACUGCUAUUUUUAAAUAUUUCUUUUAUUCUCACUCAUGAUAGACACUUUAUCCUGUGUUUUAUAUAUGUGGUUGUCUUUUUUUUUCCUGUGGAAAUAUGUAGAAGGUUAGGUUGAGCAUGUUCUUUGACAUGAGAUUUUAAGGUGCUUCUGCCAGUGCCCUGAGGUAUAACCAAUCCUGGAAUACUUAGCUACCUUGGUAUAAGAUUUUCCUGAAGACGCUUUCAGUGUUAAUUAAAACCACAAGGAAUUGAGGUGUCUUUUUUAGUUUUUGCCUCUGUGAAAGCCCAGGCUGAUAGAGAGAUGUUUCCUUGUUCCGAACCUUUUCUGGCAGACCAGUUAUUUCCUAGUUGCUAUGGUCUGAAGGUUUAUGCCUCCACUCCCAAUUUGUAUGUUGAAACUUAAUCAUCAAUGUGAUAUUAUCAGGAGGAGGAGACAUUGGGAGGUGAGUAGAUCAUGAACCCUCGUGAAUGGGAUUAAUGCCCUUAUAAAAGAGGCCUGAGAGAGACACUUGCCUCUUCCACCACUCAGUAAGAAGGUACCAUCUAUAAACCAGGCAAUGGAUCUGGAGUUCCAGAUGCCAAAUCCGUGGUACCUUGAUCUUGCAGUUCUCCACCUCCAGAACUGUGAGCAAUAAAUUUGUGAUGUUUGUAAGCUAUCUAGUUUAUGGUAUUUUAUUAGAGUAACCCAAACAGACUAAGACACAAGUCUACCCUUCUGUUAAAGACGUAGCAGUGAAUUUAUAUAGAACCUCAGUCCUAACUCUACUUUAUCGAGGCCCAACAUGUUGACUCUUGAUUGACAUGUAUCUGAAAAGAAAGGCAUCUUAGUUAAGGAAAGAAGCGAACAUUCUCUGUGCAGGUGCCCUGUUUUCCAGCUCCUUCAAUUUUAUACCACUGAAGAGUUUAUUUUCUUGUGAGCUUAGCAUGUUAGUUACAGAACAUUUAUAAUAAGUUAUGUAUUAUGUCUAAGAGUCUGGUAUCAGGAGAAUUUCAGGAUAUAUGGGCUACCAUAUGGCCAGAAUGGAAAUCUUCCACAUCUCCUAGUUGAGGUUGCUUGAGUAGGACAAGAGUAGCAUCAGGGAACCCUCUGAAGGGGAAAAGUUAACAGCAAAGGCUCUGGCAAGGUUUUUCAGAGGCCACAAUUAUAUUUUGAAGUGACUCUAUUCAAACUUUAACUCAUGGAAACAUACAAAUCAUUAUUGUAAACAUUCCAACACUCAUAUUUUCACCUUUGGGAAAUCUGAAUUCCAGUCUUACACUGAUUUUUGAAGUUCUAAAUGGAGCCACUGCUCAUCCUAAUCAUUAACCCUAGAAUUCUGCCCCUUCUUGUAUAUUUUUCAGAACCCAGCACACUGGCUUCUGCCUCAUGAUAGCUUCAUCCUCCCCAUUCCCCUUGUCUCCCUACUCAGCCAUGUUCCAUACUCUACAUAUUCCCAGAACAAAGAUUCUCUUCAAUAAUUUACUAAAACUACUCCAGUCUUUCAGUCUCCUGCCAGGAGAUAGCUACUUAAUCUGAUUUAUAAAUUUGUGUUAAUGGGUGUUAAUAGCUCAAAGUUGGGUUUCCUUCCUAGAUAAUCCUGGUGAAUUUAGCAGGGUGUAUUUAGGUUGAUAUUCCAUGUAAUACCUAUACAGUCAAGUGGCAGUAUACUCUAUGUAUGGGUUUGAGGUAUUUCCAGAAGUUUUUGACUUUUCACAAAGGAUGGGAACAAUAAUCAGAAUUGUAAUAUUAAUGUUCAUAUGAUAUUUCACAUUUUUAAAGAGUCUUUUAAAUAUUACAAUAGGUCUGUGUGACAGGUUGGAUUGUCUGUAUUUUUCAGAUAUGGAAAUAGUAAUUAAAAUCUCUAAUUGUCCUAAAUUUACAUAAUUAUGGAUUAAUGCACUCAAAAUUUGAAAUCAAGUCUUCAAUACUAUUUAUCUUUCUUUCCAAUUAGUAAGUGAAGGACUUAUAUAAAAUAAGUUGAUGUUUAAAAAAUUUAAAUUUGGAAUAAAGAGAAUGUAAAUUUGGGAUAAAGAGAAGAUAGGAGGAAGGUAACUACAUGGGAAAGCAAAGGUGAUAUGAAAGAGAAGAUAAUGGCACAGAAUGGAAAGUAAUGGCAAGAAAAGUGAAAUUCUGACGGACAGAACUUUUAACUUUUCUACACUUUUGCCUAAGGAAAAUAUUAAAUGGAGUUGCCUUCCAUUUGCCCAGGCCCCUUUAUAUAGCACUCAUAUUGAGAUUGAAAUUAUGUAUUCAUUGUUCUUUCUUUUACGUUUCUUUCAAAGAAAUAUAGAAGUAAAUUACAAGGAAAUAACUUCUCAGCAUUGACUAAAAGAGACUCAACUCUUUUAACCUAGGGGAAAGAGUUUUGAAAGAGAGAAAUUAUGAGAAAACAGUUUGAAAAGAUUUUUCAUCUCUAUGAAAAUAAAAAAGCUGUAAUAAGCAUAUACAGGUACCAUGGUUUUCUGCAGGAGUUUUCUAUUAAAAUUUUUAAGUGUCAGCCUAACAAGGGAACAGUUCAUGCAUCUGUAAAAUUACACUUGCUAAUAAUGCAUUUUCAGUGAGAAAUGCUCUUAAUUCUCACUCCACUGCAACUCACAAAGUGAUUGUAGGCAGUUGUCAUAGUAUAGCUAUAGCUAUUCCCACUUAGGUUAUAACCUCUUGUGAGCUAGUGCCACUAAUGUGUGAGAUGUUUUGUGUUUUUAGAUGUCUUUGUUAUUAUAUUAAUUAUUGAUUUUGCAGACCAGUGCUUAAAAAAGACACUCUGAAACUGUGACAUCAGUAUUUCUUGUCUGAGUCAAGGACGAUGUCUUUCAUACUGUAAGUCUUCUAUAAUCAAUAACUUACUCUGAAUUGAAUUAAAUAUGUUAAAACAUUUUUCCAGAAAAAAAAAAGAUGCAUUACAGAUCAAAGGUGACAAUAAAAUUGGCAUUGGCAAUCUUUUCCCCUCUGGUCCUUCCUAAAAUAGAUGCUAGCUGAGGUCUUCCACCCCCAAACCCUUUUCUCGAGUUAACGAGUUGGUGAAAUGAUUGCAUUUUAUCACAUUUACGAUGCCAUUGAUUGUAAGAUGUGUAUUAUUUUAUGUAUACUAAGAAAAAAUAUACUGAUUAUAAUUGCAGAUAUAGGAAAAUAUCCAUGUUAGAACUGAUGAAAUUUGAUAGAUCAAAUCGAAUAGAAAAUUAAGUUCCUUAUAGCCUCUGUAUAUUAGACCUUUGUCAGAUGCAUAGUUUGCAAAUAUUUUCUCC